AGGUGGGAGGGACGUUGAUGUGAGGCGUGGUCCUGAGUUCUCCUGAGGGCAGGUGAGGGCAGUACAGGGCAGGGAAUGUGGGGCUGGGGCAAGGGCUGCUGCCAACUCUUGACCAGAGGGGACACAGAGCAGGUGGAGGAGGGUCUCACCCAGACCAGACCCCAGGCAGGUCAACAAGCUUGGGGGUCCCUGCUGAGGUGGGGACACAGUGGAGGUGCAGGGAGCCAAGAAUGAGAGGACCUUCCCAUAGGCAGGGACGCAGCCACGUGCAGGGGGCCUGGCCUAGCUGGGGACACAGCCAGGAGCAGGGAGCAGGGGGCACUCACUCAAGGGAAGACAUCUACAGGUGCAGGCAGGAGGGAGCUUCACCUAGGCUGGGUCAAAGAACAGGUGCAGGGGCCAUGAGGGGCCUCCCAGGCGGACACACAGUGCAGGUUCAGUGGGGGUCUCACCCCAGUGGGGACACAGUGCAGGUGCAAUAAGCCUGGGGCCCUCACUGAGAUGGGGACACAGCAUCCAUGCAGGGAGGCGGAAAUGGGGGCCCUUGUUCAGGCAGGGACCUGGAGGGGGUGCAGGAUCUGGGAGACCCUGACUCAAGAGGGGCCAGGUGCAGGGAGCAGGUAUUGGGGUCCGGUACCCAAGAGCGCAGGUAGGAGGAGCGGAGCUCGGAUGGAGGCUCUGAAGAGCUGGGCCAGUCUCCAGCGCCCAGGGCUGGCCGAGCGUGGCCAGUGGAUCCGGGUGUGUCACAUGACGGGAUGAUGCCAGGCUGUGGGGCAGGGCCCCUGUGGCCAUCCUGGCUGUGCACCUGGGUGGCAGCCAGUGGGGCGGGAGCUGGGGCUGCAGCUGUGGUGUUCCCAGAGGCCCAGGUGCCCUCUCCCACACGCCUGGGCCCUCUGGGUUGUGGGAACCGGCCAGCUCCUGCUCUGUCCCCUCAGGUGUCCUGCAGGCACAGCAUCUCGGGGGGCCCAGGCCGAUGGCAGGAGUUCCUCAUGGCCGAGGAGUCUCUGCCUGGCACGCUGCUGAAGCUGGCGGCACAGGGGCUGGGCAUGCAGGCCGCCUGCACCCUGACGCGCCUCUGCUGGGCCUGGGAGCUCAGUGACCUGCACCUGCUGCAGAGCCUCAUGGCCCAGAGCUGCAGCUCGGCCCUGCGCACAUCCGUGCCCCACGGGGCGCUUGUGGAGGCCGCCUGCGCCUUUUGUUUCCAUCUGACCCUCCUGCACCUGCGGCACAGUCCUCCCGCCUACAGCGGGCCCGCUGUGGCUCUGUUGGUCACCGUCACGGCCUACACGGCCGGGCCCUUCACGUCUGCCUUCUUCAACCCUGCCCUGGCCGCCUCUGUGACCUUUGCCUGCUCGGGACACACCUUACUGGAGUACGUGCAGGUGUACUGGCUGGGCCCUCUGACAGAGGAGCAGCAUGGGGAGGUCAUGGAGCCCCCUCUUGGACCUAGAUCUGGGGAUUCUGGCCCCUGGCUUCAGAGGCCCAGGUGGAGCCCACACCUUCUCCUGCACCUGCUCUCAGACACUCGGCUCCACCUCACUGAGGUACCAGAAGGGCAGCUGGGUUCCUAUGGAAUUCUGGAAGCUUUUUUCAGCUUCUGCUGGCUCUACACUGGGGAGGUCUCAGGGGCAAUGCCUCAGCCUCCCCUUGGGGGGAAAGACAGGAGCUGGGGGUCUCUCAGGCACCUGGCCCUGCGAUGGUGACACUGACGUCAUCGUGAUUUGUCGCCAUGGUUCUGAUGUGGUCACAGUCUCUCAGGCAUGUGCAGGGUCCUAGGAAGCAUACGAAGUGCAUCAGGAACCCCCUCCUGCCCCCGUUGCCGAGGCAGCACUGCCCUCUGCUAGGAACAGCUCCGUGUUGGCCUCUCUGUCCCCACACACUGGGCCUGCAGGGCUUCUCCGAGACUCUUCAGUUCAGGUAUCAACCCUGGGCUGUCUCCUGGGAUGUGGGGGGCGGAUGUUCUUUCCUUGCCUCCCCACGCUCCUCCUGCGGAUCCUUCACUCCGGGUGGGUCGGCCUCUUCCUCCUGAUCAGCUCCAGAGCCCCCUCUAGUUCCCUGGCAUGGAAACACGGCCCGGGUGAGCUGUGGUGGCCCCGGAGGCCUCUCCGCUCCUGCACAGGCCUUGCUUCCUGCGGGUGACGAGGUCCUGGACUCUCUCCUGCCCAGGCUUCUGGGUGCUUUCCUUAGUUCAGCACCAGUGCUCUGUGUGGGCAGCGUCUCCCCCGAGGAUCCGCAGCUCCGGGUUACCCGCAGGCGUCCAUCUCCGGUAUGGUGCUGCCCUUCACUGAUCCUGGUUGUAUUUCUGUUUCCUGCUUUCCUCAUCGCCUCCUGUUUCGGUUGAUUCCUUCUUUUUGCUGGUGCCCGUCUCACAGUAGCUU